AUGAUGGGUAGAAGGAAUGACACAAAUGUGGCUGACUUCAUCCUUACGGGACUGUCAGACUCUGAAGAGGUCCAGAUGGCUCUGUUUAUGCUAUUUCUCCUCAUAUACCUAAUUACUAUGCUGGGGAAUGUGGGGAUGCUAUUGAUAAUCCGCCUGGACCUCCAGCUUCACACUCCCAUGUAUUUUUUCCUUACUCACCUGUCAUUUAUUGACCUCAGUUACUCAACUGUCGUCACACCUAAAACCUUAGCGAACUUACUGACUUCCAACUAUAUUUCCUUCACGGGCUGCUUUGCCCAGAUGUUCUGUUUUGUCUUCUUGGGUACUGCUGAAUGUUAUCUUCUCUCCUCAAUGGCCUAUGAUCGCUAUGCAGCGAUCUGCAGUCCUCUACACUACACAGUUAUUAUGCCCAAAAGGCUCUGCCUCGCUCUCAUCACUGGGCCUUAUGUGAUUGGCUUUAUGGACUCCUUUGUCAAUGUGGUUUCCAUGAGCAGAUUGCAUUUCUGUGACUCAAACAUAAUUCAUCACUUUUUCUGUGACACUUCCCCAAUUUUAGCUCUGUCCUGCACUGACACAGACAACACUGAAAUGCUGAUAUUCAUUAUCGCUGGUUCCACCCUGAUGGUGUCCCUUAUCACAAUAUCUGCAUCCUAUGUGUCCAUUCUCUCUACCAUCCUGAAAAUUAAUUCCACUUCAGGAAAGCAGAAAGCUUUCUCUACUUGCGUCUCUCAUCUCUUGGGAGUCACCAUCUUCUAUGGAACUAUGAUUUUUACUUACUUAAAGCCAAGAAAGUCUUAUUCCUUGGGAAGAGAUCAAGUGGCUCCUGUGUUUUAUACUAUUGUGAUUCCCAUGCUGAAUCCACUCAUUUAUAGUCUUAGAAACAGAGAAGUGAAAAAUGCUCUCAUUAGAGUCAUGCAGAGAAGACAGGACUCCAGGUAG